ACAACCCGGCGAUCGAAAAGAUUCUUAGGAACGCCGUACCAGCCGCGUCUCUCAGGACAGCAGGCCCCUGUCCUUCUGUCGGGCGCCGCUCAGCCGUGCCCUCCGCCCCUCAGAAUCUCGCUCCGUUGCCCAGGCUGGAGUGCAGUGGCGUGAUCUCGGCUCACUGCAACCUCUGCCUCCUGCCUCAGCCUCCCAAGUAGGUGGAACUACAGGCGCGUGCCACCACCCCUGGCUAAUUUUUUAUAGCUUUAGCAGAGACAGGGUUUUAUGAUGUUAGCCACAAUGGUCUCCAUUUCCUGACCUUGUGAUCCACCCGCCUCGGCCUCCCAAAGUGUGGGGGUUACAGGCGUGAGCCACCGCACCCGGCCUUUUUUUUUGAGACGGAGUUUCACUCUUGUUGCCCGGGCUGGAGUGCAAUGGCACAAUCUCAGCUUACUGCAACCUCCGCCUCCCAGGUUCAAGUGAUUCUCCUGUCUCACCCUCCCAAGUAGCUGGGAUUACAGGCUCCUGCCACCAUGCCUGGCUAAUUUGUGUAUUUUUAGUAGAGACGGGUUUCGUCAUGUUGGUCAGGCUGGUCUCGAACCCUGACCUCAGGUGAUCUACCCUCCUCAGCCUCCCAAAGUGCUGGGAUUACAGGUGUGAGCCACCUUGCCCAGCUUCGUGUCUUUUUUUUUUAAAUUAUUUUUUCUUCAGGUAGCCUCCCGAGCCAGAGUAGGCUCAGAGACACCCUUUUCCAUGUUUUUGUUGGCCAUUUGUGUUUCUUUGAGAAAUUUUUUUUUUUUUUUUUGAGACAAAGUCUGGCUGUUUCGCCCAGGCUAGAGUGCAAUGGCACGAUGUCGGCUCACUGCAACCUCCACCUCCCGGGUUCAAGCGAUUCUCCUGCAUCAGCCUCCCAAGUAGCUGGGAUUACAGGUUCUUUUUCUAAUUCCAAAUAAACUUGCAAGAGGACUAUGAAAGAUUAUGAUGAACUUCUCAAAUAUUAUGAAUUACAUGAAACUAUUGGGACAGGUGGCUUUGCAAAGGUCAAACUUGCCUGCCAUAUCCUUACUGGAGAGAUGGUAGCUAUAAAAAUCAUGGAUAAAAACACACUAGGGAGUGAUUUGCCCCGGAUCAAAACGGAGAUUGAGGCCUUGAAGAACCUGAGACAUCAGCAUAUAUGUCAACUCUACCAUGUGCUAGAGACAGCCAACAAAAUAUUCAUGGUUCUUGAGUACUGCCCUGGAGGAGAGCUGUUUGACUAUAUAAUUUCCCAGGAUCGCCUGUCAGAAGAGGAGACCCGGGUUGUCUUCCGUCAGAUAGUAUCUGCUGUUGCUUAUGUGCACAGCCAGGGCUAUGCUCACAGGGACCUCAAGCCAGAAAAUUUGCUGUUUGAUGAAUAUCAUAAAUUAAAGCUGAUUGACUUUGGUCUCUGUGCAAAACCCAAGGGUAACAAGGAUUACCAUCUACAGACAUGCUGUGGGAGUCUGGCUUAUGCAGCACCUGAGUUAAUACAAGGCAAAUCAUAUCUUGGAUCAGAGGCAGAUGUUUGGAGCAUGGGCAUACUGUUAUAUGUUCUUAUGUGUGGAUUUCUACCAUUUGAUGAUGAUAAUGUAAUGGCUUUAUACAAGAAGAUUAUGAGAGGAAAAUAUGAUGUUCCCAAGUGGCUCUCUCCCAGUAGCAUUCUGCUUCUUCAACAAAUGCUGCAGGUGGACCCAAAGAAACGGAUUUCUAUGAAAAAUCUAUUGAACCAUCCCUGGAUCAUGCAAGAUUACAACUAUCCUGUUGAGUGGCAAAGCAAGAAUCCUUUUAUUCACCUCGAUGAUGAUUGCGUAACAGAACUUUCUGUACAUCACAGAAACAACAGGCAAACAAUGGAGGAUUUAAUUUCACUGUGGCAGUAUGAUCACCUCACGGCUACCUAUCUUCUGCUUCUAGCCAAGAAGGCUCGGGGAAAACCAGUUCGUUUAAGGCUUUCUUCUUUCUCCUGUGGACAAGCCAGUGCUACCCCAUUCACAGACAUCAAGUCAAAUAAUUGGAGUCUGGAAGAUGUGACCGCAAGUGAUAAAAAUUAUGUGGCGGGAUUAAUAGACUAUGAUUGGUGUGAAGAUGAUUUAUCAACAGGUGCUGCUACUCCCCGAACAUCACAGUUUACCAAGUACUGGACAGAAUCAAAUGGGGUGGAAUCUAAAUCAUUAACUCCAGCCUUAUGCAGAACACCUGCAAAUAAAUUAAAGAACAAAGAAAAUGUAUAUACUCCUAAGUCUGCUGUAAAGAAUGAAGAGUACUUUAUGUUUCCUGAGCCAAAGACUCCAGUUAAUAAGAACCAGCAUAAGAGAGAAAUACUCACUACGCCAAAUCGUUACACUACACCCUCAAAAGCUAGAAACCAGUGCCUGAAAGAAACUCCAAUUAAAAUACCAGUAAAUUCAACAGGAACAGACAAGUUAAUGACAGGUGUCAUUAGCCCUGAGAGGCGGUGCCGCUCAGUGGAAUUGGAUCUCAACCAAGCACAUAUGGAGGAGACUCCAAAAAGAAAGGGAGCCAAAGUGUUUGGGAGCCUUGAAAGGGGGUUGGAUAAGGUUAUCACUGUGCUCACCAGGAGCAAAAGGAAGGGUUCUGCCAGAGACGGGCCCAGAAGACUAAAGCUUCACUAUAACGUGACUACAACUAGAUUAGUGAAUCCAGAUCAACUGUUGAAUGAAAUAAUGUCUAUUCUUCCAAAGAAGCAUGUUGACUUUGUACAAAAGGGUUAUACACUGAAGUGUCAAACACAGUCAGAUUUUGGGAAAGUGACAAUGCAAUUUGAAUUAGAAGUGUGCCAGCUUCAAAAACCCGAUGUGGUGGGUAUCAGGAGGCAGCGGCUUAAGGGCGAUGCCUGGGUUUACAAAAGAUUAGUGGAAGACAUCCUAUCUAGCUGCAAGGUAUAAUUGAUGGAUUCUUCCAUCCUGCCGGAUGAGUGUGGGUGUGAUACAGCCUACAUAAAGACUGUUAUGAUCGCUUUGAUUUUAAAGUUCAUUGGAACUACCAACUUGUUUCUAAAGAGCUAUCUUAAGACCAAUAUCUCUUUGUUUUUAAACAAAAGAUAUUAUUUUGUGUAUGAAUCUAAAUCAAGCCCAUCUGUCAUUAUGUUACUGUCUUUUUUAAUCAUGUGGUUUUGUAUAUUAAUAAUUGUUGACUUUCUUAGAUUCACUUCCAUAUGUGAAUGUAAGCUCUUAACUAUGUCUCUUUGUAAUGUGUAAUUUCUUUCUGAAAUAAAACCAUUUGUGAAUAUA